AGUCACAUAGCUGCGUGGUACGUGACUGGAGGUGUAUCCUUGUCCUCGUCUGAAUCACGCUGAUGUGGCCCCAACCCCACCUCCCUCCCCACCCCAUGAUGUCAGAAAAAACCAGACAGAACAAAUUGGCUGAGGCCAAGAAAAAGUUUACAGACUAUCGUCAGUGGAACAUUGCUGGUGUUGGUACCGGAGCAACUGACACCAAAAAGAAGAAAAUAAAUCAUGGCACUAACCCUGAGACAACCACUUCGGGGGGCUGCCACUCGCCUGAGGAUACACAACAGAACCGAGCGCAGCUGAAAGAAGAAAAGAAGGCAAGCCACCAACAUCAGGAAGCCCUAAGGCGGGAGAUAGAGGCCCAGGAUCAUACAAUACGAAUUCUCACGUGUCAGAAAACUGAACUGGAGACAGCGCUCUAUUACAGCCAGGAUGCUGCCAGGAAAUUUGAAGAUGGGAACCUGGGCACCCCAUCAUCCUUCAACCUGGCACUUUCACAGGCCUUUAGGGGGAGUCCUUUGGGCUGUGUCUCAACCUCUCUCAUUCCAGGAGAGUCCAAGGAUCUCGCCGGCCGCUUGCAUCAUUCCUGGCACUUUGCAGGAGAGUUACAGCGGGCUCUCUCUGCUGUGUCCACACGGCACAAGAAGGCAGACAGGUACAUCGAGGAGUUAACAAAGGAGAGGGACGCCCUGAGUCUGGAACUGUACAGGAACACCAUAACCAAUGAGGAGCUGAAGAAGAAAAAUGCCGAACUACAAGAAAAACUUCCACUUGCAGAAUCUGAAAAGUCUGAGAUCCAGCUCAACGUGAAGGAGCUAAAAAGGAAACUGGAGAGGGCCAAGUUCCUGCUGCCACAGGUUCAAACCAACACUUUGCAGGAGGAGAUGUGGAGGCAGGAGGAGGAGCUACGGGAGCAGGAAAAGAAGAUACGGAAGCAGGAGGAGAAGAUGUGGAGACAGGAGGAGAGACUGCGGGAGCAGGAGGGGAAGAUGCGGGAGCAGGAGGAGAAGAUGUGGAGACAGGAGAAGAGGCUGCGAGAGCAGGAGAAGGAGCUGCGGGAGCAGGAGAAGGAGCUGCGGGAGCAGAAGGAGCUGCGGGAGCAGGAGGAGCAGAUGCAGGAGCAGGAGGAGAAGAUGUGGGAGCAGGAGGAGAAGAUGCGGGAGCAGGAAGAGAAGAUGUGGAGACAGGAGGAGAGGCUGUGGGAGCAGGAGAAGCAGAUGCGGGAGCAGGAGCAGAAGAUGCGGGACCAAGAGGAGAGGAUGUGGGAGCAGGACGAGAGGCUACGGGAGAAGGAGGAGAGGAUGCGGGAGCAGGAGAAGAUGUGGGAGCAGGUGGAGAAGAUGCGGGAGGAGAAGAAGAUGCAGGAGCAGGAGAAGAAGACGCGGGACCAGGAGGAGAAGAUGCAAGAGGAGGAGAGGAUACGGGAGCGGGAGAAGAAGAUGCGGGAAGAGGAGGAGACGAUGCGGGAGCAGGAGGAGAAGAUGCAGAAGCAGGAGGAGAAUAUGUGGGAGCAGGAAGAGAAGGAGUGGCAGCAGCAGAGGCUGCCGGAACAGAAGGAGAAGCUGUGGGAACAGGAGAAGAUGCAGGAGCAGGAGGAGAAGAUAUGGGAGCAGGAGGAGAAGAUACGGGACCAGGAGGAGAUGUGGGGGCAGGAGAAGAAGAUGUGGCGGCAGGAGAAGAUGCGGGAGCAGGAAGAUGUGGAGACAGGAGGAGAGGCUGCAGGAGCAGGAGAAGCAGAUGUGGGAGCAGGAGGAGAAGAUGCGGGAUCAGGAGCAGAAGAUGUGGGACCAGGAGGAGAGGAUGUGGGAGCAGGACGAGAGGCUGCGGGAGAAGGAGGAGAGAAUGCGGGAGCAGAAGAAGAUGUGGCAGCAGGUGGAGAAGAUGCGGGAGGAGAAGAAGACGCAGGAGCAGGAGAAGAAGACAUGGGACCAGGAGGAGAAGAUGCGAGAGGAGGAGAGGAUGCGGGAGCGGGAGAAGAAGAUGCGGGAGGAGGAGGAGAUGAUGCGGGAGCAGGAGGAGAAGAUGCAGGAGCAGGAAGAGAAGAUGCAGGAGCAGGAGGAGAAGAUGUGGGAGCAGGAAGAGAAGAUGCAGGAGCAGGAGGAGAAGAUGUGGGAGCAGGAGGAGAAGAUGUGGGAGCAGGAAGAAGAUGUGGGAGCAGCAGAGGCUGCCGGAACAGAAGGAGAAGCUGUGGGAACACGAGAAGAUGCAAGAGCAGGAGAUCAGGAGCAGAAGAUGUGGGACCAGAAGGAGAGGAUGUGGGAGCAGGACGAGAGGCUGCGGGAGAAGGAGGAGAGAAUGCGGGAGCAGAAGAUGUGGCAGCAGGUGGAGAAGAUGCGGGAGGAGAAGAAGACGCAGGAGGAGAAGAUGCAGGAGCAGGAAGAAAAGAUGCAGGAGCAGGAGGAGGAGAUGUGGGAGCAGGAGGAGAAGAUGUGGGAGCAGGAAGAGAAGAUGUGGGAGCAGGAGGAGAAGAUGCGGGAGCAGGAGGAGAAGAUGCGGGAGCAGGAGGAGAAGAUGCAGGGCCAGGAGGAGAAGAUGCGGGAGCAGGAGGAGAAGAUGCGGGGCCAGGAGGAGAAGAUGCGGGAGCAGGAGGAGAAGAUGCGGGGCCAGGAGGAGAAGAUGUGGGGCCAGGAGGAGAAGAUGUGGGGGCAGGAGGAGAAGAUGUGGGGGCAGGAGGAGAUGAUGCGAGAGAAGGAGGAGAGGAUACGAGAUCAGAAAGAGAAGAUGCAGGAGAGGCUGCCAGAGCACGAGGAGCGGUGCUCAGAGCCCUGCCUCCCUCCCUCCAAAGUUCUUUGUAAUAUGAGCCACACUGGCAGUGUGGAGCCUGCAGGAGGAGAGGCUGGGGAGGGUUCUCCGCAGGACAACCCCACUGCACAGGAGAUCAUGCAGCUGUUUUGUGGGAUGAAGAACGCCCAGCAGUGCCCAGGAUUAGGCAGUACCUCCUGCAUCCCAUUCUUCUACCGAGGAGACAAGAGAAAGAUGAAGAUCAUCAAUAUCUAAAAGUUGGCACUGUCAACAAGGCCUACAGAAGCAUAAGCCGCCAUGUCACUGUGUGAAUAUAGUCUGAGCACAAACUUGAAAAAAAAAAAAAAAAAGAAAAGAAAAUUUACUUUAAAUUGUGGUAAAAUACUAGCCAGGCCUUGUGGCCGAAACCUACAACCACAGCACUUUGGGAGACCUAGAGGGGGUGGAUCACCUGAGGUCAGGAGUUCAAGACCAGCCUGGCCAACAUGAUGAAACCCCGUCUCUACUAAAAAUACAAGUUAGCCGGGCGUGGUUGUGCACGCCUGUAAUCACAGCUACUCAGGAGGCUGCAGUGAGCCAAGAUCACACCACCGCAUUCCAGCCUGGAUGAGAGCGAGAUUCCAUCUCAAAAAAAAAAAAAAAAAAAGUUUCUACCUGAGGACUCUGAUAUCUAUGUAUGUUUCUAUUGUUUUUCUUCUUGGUCUUUCUCAUUUAGUCUUGUUUUGUUUUAUGGCAUUCCUAGUAAACUUUUAUGUGCCUCCA